UGCGGGCGUGGACUCCUCAUUCCGGCUGUGGCCGCGCCGCUGCGGGGCCUGAGGCCCUCUUGGGUUUUGGUUCAGCGUUAGUUAACGGUUAACCCGCCAAGGCGGGCUUCCGCCCAGGCACAGGAGACUCACCGAGCUUGUUCACCUUGAAACUUGGGCCACACCUGAGACCUGCCACCUAAGGGGGGUACGCGGGUCGUUUUUAACAAGCUUUCAUGGCAUUUGUGCCAUGAAAGCUCUAAAGUAUAGAAGCUGCUCCAGGGCUUCCGCAGCCCCGGCCGUCCUGGAGAUACUCGCCUCCUGGAGUCUGUGUCGAGAAUUUGCAGCACCUGGACAGCCACGUGCAGUCUCAGAACUGCAGGCGGUCUUUACCGAAAUGUUAAACACAACUUGAAGUUAGGCAGGAUAACUGCCAGAGCUGGAUGGACCUUAGAGGUGCCAGCUAACGCGCUGUGAGCGUUUUCUGCGGUUAGGCCUGCUCUAAACAUUUGACAUGUGUUAAAGCAUUUAUGUGCUUUACCCACACCCCUAUGUGGCGGGCCCUUCUUAAAGUAAAAGAAACUGCAGCACAGCGAAGUUAAGCAACUUGCCCCAAAUCACGCAGAACUGGGAUGCAAACCCAGGUCUAGCUCACUCGUGAUCACAAUUCAACAUCAUACGAUGGUGCUGAUUUCCAGAGCAGCUCUGUGACUUUAUAUAAAAUUAUUGGGCAAGCGUUCAAUUGUAAACAUUCGUGAACAUAGCUGUUGCACAUUAGCGUUCCUUUUUUUUUUUAAUUCAGGACCAUCUUUGGUGACAAAUAUAAAUAUCAAUACUAUAUAUAUCACCAAUAUACAUAUUUGCUUUGCUAAAAGGUUUCUGUGUCUUCAGGAUAGUUUACUUGCAAGCCUCAUGUUUUUAUAAAAACGUGGGUGCUACCUGAAUAAAACUAAUGCCUACCCGUUGGCGGUUUUGUGAAGACUAAUGAACUAUUAUAUUCAAAGGGUCCAAGCAGUAGGCAUUUACUAAAGGACAGCUAGUUUUAUCUGUUAUUAUUCUGCCAUUCAGAGAGAUACCAAAACUACUCUCUAAGGCAUUUCUCUUCCCUGCAUGUAAAAGCAAGGGUGUCAUACUUGAGAUAAGCAUUCUGAUAAUGUGUAGGCAAAGUUUCCACACUUGGUAAAAGCAUCUUAGUCAUGGUUCAAGACGAGUGACAACCCCAGUCUUCUCUGCUCCUUUUUUAUCAGUCCCGUAAAAGUUCACCAGUUUGUCGGGUUGGAGGCAAACCUUGCAAAAACUGUUACCACCUAUUUGCAAUUCAAGGAGAAUAUAAGACAGAGAAGAAAGCUGUGAAUGAAUUUCAUUUGAUUAGCAAUAGAUUGGACACUCUACUGAUCUUGCCUCUCUACAACCUCUCUUCCACCUGACCUCUAAAUGUUGAAGUGUUUCAGGAAUUGUCUUAGACCUUCUUCCUUAUCUACACUUCCUCUCCAAUAUGGAAUUCUCUUCCCCAAGCUGUUGGCAUGUCUAGUUCAUUUGCAUUUUGGGCAUUUCAGCUCAGCUGUCAUCUCAGUGACCAGUUUUUAUCUGAGCAUGAAUCUUGAUGGCUCUGCACAAGAUCCUGAAAAGAGGGAAUAUUCUUCUGUGUGUGUGGGCAGAGAAGAUGACAUUAAAAAAUCUGAAAGAAUGACAGCUGUUGUCCAUGAUAGAGAAGUGGUCAUUUUCUACCACAAGGGAGAAUAUCAUGCUAUGGAUAUUCGCUGUUACCACUCAGGAGGACCUUUACAUUUGGGAGAUAUAGAGGAUUUUGAUGGACGACCGUGUAUAGUUUGCCCCUGGCAUAAAUACAAAAUUACUUUGGCAACAGGAGAAGGUCUGUACCAGUCUAUAAACCCUAAAGAUCCAUCAGCAAAACCCAAGUGGUGCUCCAAAGGAAUAAAGCAAAGGAUUCACACAGUGACAGUAGACAACGGAAAUAUUUAUGUGACUCUUUCUAAUGAACCUUUUAAGUGUGACUCUGAUUUUUAUGCCACUGGAGACUUCAAAGUAAUUAAGAGUUCUUCCUGAUAAAAAAUAUAUAGAAAUGAAAAAUGUUGUGUAUGCUUGAAAACAUUUUUAGAAUAACUCUGCUUCAGUUUUAAAGGUGAUGAAAUUUUUCAACAUAGGCACAACUGUUUAAAAUUCACAUACAUUUGAGAGGUUUAAGAGCACACAUACUUAGUAUGAUGUAAGGAUUAUCAUCAGGAUCAAUAGAAUACAUUUUAUCGAAUCUUCUGGAUUAAUUAGAAACCUGAAGGUUAUAGGUUUGGGAUGUUCUGUUUAAGAAGGAUAAAAAUAAAUUUGGAGUAAACAAAUAAUAGGUAAAAAUUAAGGAUUAGUAAGAAAAAAUUUUUUAAUUUAAAAAAUUUAAUUUUUAAAAUAGGAAAAAAUCCCUGUUUGAUGUAGCAGACUUAAUUCUGGAAAAGUUUUAGUAUAUACAAAGUAAACAGACUAUAUAAUGAACUUCCAUCACUCAGCUUUAACAGUUAUCAGCAUUCUUCCAUUCUUGUUUUAUUUAUACCUCUGUGGAUUUGCUACCUCUCCUAUUUGAUUGUUAUUUUUACAUUUUUAGGAAAGUUUAAAUACAUUGAAAUGUUCACCUCUGAACUGUGCAACCUUCCUAAAUAACAGACUUUUUAUACUUAAAAAAUGCCUCCAAAAAUGAGAUAGGUUUACCUGCUGAACUUGAAAAUAAGAAACUUAACCACUGUUAAGUGAUCUGUGAUCAAGGCAGAUCUUGAAGUAAGGAAGCCAGACACAGCUGCUGCCCAGCCAUGAGAGAUGUAAAGUCUCCUAUUCAGUGAGCCAAUGUUCUUUGAAUGCCUAUAUGAAAUUUUCAAAUAAAGAUUUUUAAAAACGUUUUAGAACUUUGUGAAUGUAGGCACAACUAAGUGUCUCCUAUAAAUAUUAUAGAGAGGAGAUCUAGGGUUUUGUUCCUUGGAGUUCCCGAGCAAGGUUGAUGUUCAGUUGGUUCACCCUGGUUUUAUCAUGUCAGUUAUUUAUGGUCAGUACCAUUCAGUUGCAAUGAUGGUCAUACCGUACCAGUUGUAAUGUAUUUAAAAUAACACCCCAAGCACCCACCAUGCAAAAAUCAGCAGCACAUAGUGGUGAUUUUUGCAUGGUCAGUGCUCAUGCAAAAAUCACCACUAUGUGGGACCAGAAAUAGCUAAAAUGAGUAGAUGAUGAAUUCAGAGUGAGAAGAACUGUCAAGAUUGGAACCUAGUCUCAAAGCACAGUAGUAUUUUUAAAGGAAUAGAAUUAAGAAUCUAAAUCUAAUACUUAACAUUCUAAGGAGCCGACCUGGACUCUUUCUCUUGGUUAUUAUAAAAAUAGUAAAUGAGUAAGGUCCGUAUAGUAAAGACUCUGCUUACUUACCUUUACUACAUAUUAUUACACUUCCUUUUCUGUUGGAGUUUGGAUAGCAUGAGUAGCACUUGGUCCUCAUUUCUCAGACAACCAACGAACCAGACUUGGGCUUUUUAUAGAUACUGUUUGUGGUAGCAGCUACUUACUAAGUACAGAAAAUGUACUAUCUCUCAGGAAGGUACAUCCCAGUCUAUUCUAUCAUGUGAUAAUCCUUCAAUGCCCAGUCAGGUCUUAACACAUGUCCAGAAUAUAAAGUGUACAGAAGAAAUCAAAGUACUUUCUUCAGGCAAAAACUAGCCCUGGUUUGCAGGAAUAAUUACAGAAAUAUUUUCUCAUAGGAGCCACUGGCAAUAAUGAGUAGUGUGCACUUGAUUUUUCAUUCUAAAUUUGUAUCUCUAAAUCUAGAAAUAAAAAUCAUAUCAUGUACUGUCUUCA